AACAUAAAAGUGUACCUAUUUGCAGUCACUACCUCUAUCACCACCACCAGCAGAGCCUGAGCUGAGGAAACCACGGUUCUCAAUACCCAGCACACCCACUUCCAACUAUCUGUUAAAACAUGGUGGAUUACUAUGAAGUUCUAGGACUGCAAAGAUAUGCUUCACCUGAGGACAUUAAAAAAGCUUAUCAUAAAGUGGCACUUAAAUGGCACCCUGAUAAAAAUCCAGAAAAUAAAGAAGAAGCAGAGAGAAAAUUCAAAGAAGUAGCUGAGGCAUACGAGGUAUUAUCAAAUGAUGAGAAACGGGACAUUUAUGAUAAAUAUGGCACAGAAGGAUUAAACGGAGGUGGAAGUCAUUUUGAUGAUGAAUGUGAGUACGGCUUCACAUUCCAUAAGCCAGAUGAUGUUUUUAAAGAAAUUUUUCAUGAAAGGGAUCCAUUUUCUUUUCACUUCUUUGAAGACUCGCUUGAGGACCUGUUAAAUCGUCCAGGAAGCUCCUAUGGAAACAGAAACAGAGAUGCAGGAUACUUUUUCUCCACUGCCAGUGAAUAUCCAAUUUUUGAGAAAUUUUCUUCAUAUGAUACAGGAUAUACAUCACAGGGUUCAUUGGGGCAUGAAGGCCUUACUUCUUUCUCUUCCCUGGCUUUUGAUAAUAGUGGGAUGGACAACUACAUAUCUGUUACAACUUCAGACAAAAUCGUUAAUGGCAGAAAUAUUAAUACAAAGAAAAUUAUUGAAAGUGAUCAAGAAAGAGAAGCUGAAGAUAAUGGAGAGUUGACAUUUUUUCUUGUAAAUAGUGUGGCCAAUGAAGAGGGCUUUGCAAAAGAAUGCAGCUGGAGAACACAGUCAUUCAACAACUAUUCACCAAAUUCUCACAGCUCCAAACAUGUAUCUCAAUAUACUUUCGUGGACAAUGAUGAGGGAGGUAUAUCUUGGGUUACCAGCAACAGAGAUCCCCCUAUUUUCUCAGCAGGAGUCAAAGAGGGUGGUAAGAGGAAAAAAAAGAAGCGUAAAGAGGUGCAAAAGAAGUCUACCAAAAGGAAUUGUUAAAUUGACUCUUCAAAUAUAUAACAUUUGAACACAAUUGUGUGUGUUUUGGUUAAUCACAAAUUUUGUAGAUAACACUUAAUACUAUACUAAGAGCUUUUCAACACUUUUAGCAGGAUUGUGGACAUUUGGUUAGUAGUUUUUUUGAAUGGGUAUGUCAGAAAAGGAUGAGUUUGUGGUGACAGUUGGUGCUAAUAAGAAUUUGCCUGGGCAGUAUAGUGAGAUCUUUUCUCUACAAAAAAUUUAAAAAUUAGCCAAGUGUGGUGGUGUGCACCUGUAGUCCCAGCUACUCGGGAAGCUGGUAGAAAGACUGCUUGAGCCUGGAAGACAUAGGUUGCAGUGUAAUGGGAUCACGCCACUGCACUCCAGCUUGGGUGACAAAGUAAGACCCUGUCUUAAAAAAAAAAAAAAGGAAUUUGGAAAACUGCAAUGAGUUUUUUACUUUUGAAUUUUUCUUUAGUAGAGUUUAUAGCCUAUUUUUCUUUUUUCUAAUUAAAACCACUAUACAAACUUACGAAACAUGCAUAGCAUUAGAAGACAAGAAUGUAUCAAGACACACAGGUUCAGACUACACAAUUAUUCAUGAAAUGGCUGUUUUCCAAUGGAGGAACAGCAUUUGAUGCAUUAUAACUUAAAGGUACUACAAAUUAAAAAUUAAAGUAUAAAGUAUUUUAAGUUAGAAAUAGACUUAGCUGGGUGCAGUGGCUCACACCUGUAAUCCUAGCAUCUUGGGAGGCCCAGGCAGGAGGGUUGAAGUCAGAAUUUCACGACAGUCCGGGUAACAUAAUGAGACCUGUCCUCUAUGAAAAAACUUUUUUAAAAAUUUAGCUGGGUGUGGUGGUACGUGCCUGUAGGCCUAGCUACUUAGGAGGCUGAGGUGGGAGGAUUGCUUGAGCCCAGGAGUUUGAGGUUGUAGGGAGCUAUGAUCUUGCCAUUGCACUCCAGCUGAGAGUGUGACCCUGUCUCUAAAGAAAAACUAUAGAAAAUUUAAAAAAUUAAAAAACGGGUAACAUGGUAAAUUUUAUGUAGUAUAUUUUACCACAUUUUUUUUAAAGGCCAGUCUUAUCCUGAAUUCCUCAGAGCAGUCUGUAUGGUAGGCCAUCAGUGAAUCACUCCAGACAGGAAAUUUUCUAUUUUUGUUUAGAGUUUGUACACAAAAUCUACAAAUACAUUACUCUAAAAUAGCACCUAUAGCCAUUUUAAUUUAGUCAUGUUGGGAGAAAAAUAGAUGGGUUACAAAUACAUCAGAUAUCGAGCAAAUGGUUUGAGUUACAUCUAGCAGCACUAAAACUUAUUCAACUUUGGCCAAAUACAAAUGCGAAAUUAGAAAAAAAUUAUAAUAUCUGCUAUUUUUAAAAGACAGCUAUAGUCAAGAGCUUGUGUUUUGUAUCGGUAUUUGAUUUUUAGUGGGCAGAUGGGAGAAGGAAAGGUUAUUUAUUCUAUAGAAGAGACUGCGGACAAUUAGUAUUCAAAGUUUAUUUUCAGAAAAUAAAAUAAUAAAAGCCCAGGGUAUUUUAAA